GUUUCCGAAGGGACCACCGGGAACAGACGGAUCGGCAGGGCGGGGCGGAACGGUGAGUUAUGCUGAGCGACUCUGCUCCUGGCCUCCUGGAGGCUCGAGACCCCCGCGCCAGGAGCGAGGUGGGAGAGUAGCUACGUGGGGUAUUAGUUUCCUCGCUCCUCAAGGGGAAUCAUAAUUUACGGGCGGUUGCGUGCCCUAGACUGACUGCUCUCCCCUUUCAGUGAGGACUGUGCUUCCUCCGAGGGAGUUGCGGGCCGGGACAUGCGGACCGAGCAUAUUUCUAGGUCUAGGGACAAGGGACUUGGAAUCCUGCCUCGGACUUUGUCGGAGGGUUUUAGUGACUUCUCUACGUAGCUCCCUCAUUGUCUCUCAUCUUUUGGCUCCCCUGUCAAGGACCAUCCCCCAUUCUAGGACUUCGAUGUGUGAUGCUUUGAUCAAAGGAUUGACAUUCCUUUUCUAAGUGUUUGCUGUCAGCUUUCAGCCACUUGAUUGGUUUGGAAUCGGAGCCUUUUCUCCUGCGAUUCCAGGUGUCCCUAAGGUAUCAGUGUUAUCCAGAACCAAGAACUCAGUGGAGGAAUGAAAAAGGCAGCAUCUUUAAAAUAAUGUUUAUUGGAAGGGGUUGCAAGAGCUUGCGAAGUCAUGAAGAACAAAGUUUUUUAGAGCCAUUAUGAAAUGGCAACGAUAAUACUGCACUCUAUGUGAACAGUUUCUGUUUCCUUCAUCUGGGGCACGUGCAUAUGAUCAACUUUGGACUUCUUUUGAGAUUGCCAGGUGAGGCCAUCUACUGAAACACAGAAGCAAUUUUAAAAGAAAAUGGAGGAAGUAUAACUGAUCUUUGCAGAAAGUGGGGAAGUGAGUUGACCAGAGAAGGAUGAGAGAAUUGCCAAGUUGUACUGAACGCCAAGCUGAGAAUGGUGAUUCUGAAGAUAGAAUAUCAACACAGUUACACCAAGUUGCUGACCUCUUUAUGACUGCUGUAGAAAGUAAACUUCUUUCACUAUAUGGAUAUUUGCCGGUAAGGAAGGAAAAGUAACAGAGAUUAGAGAAGGCAACAGAAAAGGGGGAGUAAAGGCGUUUGCAAUGGCUGCUACUGUGAACUUGGAACUUGAUCCCAUUUUUUUGAAAGCACUAGGUUUCUUGCAUUCAAAGAGUAAAGAUUCUGCUGAAAAGCUAAAAGCACUGCUUGAUGAAUCUUUGGCUCGGGGCAUUGAUUCCAGUUACCGUCCAUCUCAAAAGGAUGUGGAGCCACCCAAAAUUUCAAGCACAAAAAACAUUUCCAUUAAGCAAGAGCCCAAAAUAUCAUCCAGUCUUCCUUCUGGUAAUAAUAAUGGCAAGGUCCUCACAACUGAAAAGGUAAAGAAGGAAGCUGAAAAGAGACCUGCUGAUAAAAUGAAAUCAGACAUCACUGAAGGAGUUGAUAUUCCAAAGAAACCUAGAUUGGAGAAACCAGAAACACAGUCAUCUCCCAUUACUGUCCAAAGUAGCAAGGAUUUACCUAUGGCUGACCUUUCCAGUUUUGAGGAGACCAGUGCUGAUGAUUUUGCCAUGGAGAUGGGAUUGGCCUGCGUUGUUUGUAGGCAAAUGAUGGUGGCAUCUGGCAAUCAAUUAGUAGAAUGUCAGGAGUGCCAUAAUCUCUACCACCGAGAUUGUCAUAAACCCCAGGUGACAGACAAGGAAGCGAAUGACCCUCGCCUGGUGUGGUAUUGUGCCCGAUGUACCAGACAAAUGAAAAGAAUGGCUCAAAAAACUCAGAAACCACCGCAGAAACCAGCCCCUGCAGUUGUUUCUGUAACUCCAGCUGUCAAAGAUCCAUUGGUUAAGAAACCAGAAACUAAACUGAAACAAGAGACAACUUUUCUAGCGUUUAAGAGAACAGAAGUCAAGACAUCCACAGUUAUUUCAGGAAAUUCUUCUAGUGCCAGCGUUUCCUCGUCAGUAACUAGUGGCUUAACUGGAUGGGCAGCUUUUGCAGCCAAAACUUCCUCUGCUGGUCCUUCAACAGCAAAAUUGAGUUCAACAACACAAAACAAUACUGGGAAACCUGCUACUUCGUCAGCUAACCAGAAACCUGUGGGUUUGACUGGUCUGGCAACAUCAUCCAAAGGUGGAAUAGGUUCCAAAAUAGGUUCCAAUAACAGCACUACGCCCACUGUACCUUUAAAACCACCUCCACCUCUAACCUUGGGUAAAACUGGCCUUAGUCGCUCAGUUAGUUGUGACAAUGUCAGCAAAGUAGGUCUUCCUAGUCCAAGUAGUUUAGUUCCAGGAAGCAGCAGCCAACUAAGUGGGAAUGGAAAUAGUGGAACAUCAGGACCUAGUGGAAGUACUACCAGCAAAACUACUUCAGAAUCCAGCAGCUCUCCCUCAGCAUCCCUUAAAGGCCCAACUUCACAAGAAUCACAGCUCAAUGCUAUGAAGCGAUUACAGAUGGUCAAGAAGAAAGCUGCCCAAAAGAAACUCAAGAAGUAAUGUGGCCAAGUAGGUUUUUGUAUCAUAUUAGCCUAAAGAUGAAAGGCUUAUUAUUAUGAUAUAAUCUGUAAUACACUGUAAUUUAAUAAAAGUCUUCAUAAUCAAA